CCCAGUCUAUCCAUUCUGCCUUUCCUGUCUUUGAGGUUCCUAGCAAGCCCAAGGGUAUGUUAGAAGAAAAGACCACAGAUUAUUGUACUCUCUGACCUUCCUGUCCUAGAUGUCCACAAGAGCAUGGAAGGCAACAAGACAUGGAUCACAGACAUCACCUUGCCGCGAUUCCAGGUUGGUCCAGCACUGGAGAUUCUCCUCUGUGGACUUUUCUCUGCCUUCUAUACACUCACCCUGCUGGGGAAUGGGGUCAUCUUUGGGAUUAUCUGCCUGGACUGUAAGCUUCACACACCCAUGUACUUCUUCCUCUCACACCUGGCCAUUGUUGACAUAUCCUAUGCUUCCAACUAUGUCCCCAAGAUGCUGACGAAUCUUAUGAACCAGGAAAGCACCAUCUCCUUUUUUCCAUGCAUAAUGCAGACAUUCUUGUAUUUGGCUUUUGCUCACGUAGAGUGUCUGAUUUUGGUGGUGAUGUCCUAUGAUCGCUAUGCGGACAUCUGCCACCCCUUACGUUACAAUAGCCUCAUGAGCUGGAGAGUGUGCACUGUCCUGGCUGUGGCUUCCUGGGUGUUCAGCUUCCUCCUGGCUCUGGUCCCUUUAGUUCUCAUCCUGAGCCUGCCCUUCUGCGGGCCUCAUGAAAUCAACCACUUCUUCUGUGAAAUCCUGUCUGUCCUCAAGUUGGCCUGUGCUGACACCUGGCUCAACCAGGUGGUCAUCUUUGCAGCCUGCGUGUUCAUCCUGGUGGGGCCACUCUGCCUGGUGCUGGUCUCCUACUUGCGCAUCCUGGCCGCCAUCUUGAGGAUCCAGUCUGGGGAGGGCCGCAGAAAGGCCUUCUCCACCUGCUCCUCCCACCUUUGCGUGGUGGGACUCUUCUUUGGCAGCGCCAUUGUCACGUACAUGGCCCCCAAGUCCCGCCAUCCUGAGGAGCAGCAGAAAGUUCUUUCCCUGUUUUACAGCCUUUUCAAUCCAAUGCUGAACCCCCUGAUAUAUAGCCUAAGGAAUGCAGAGGUCAAGGGCGCCCUGAGGAGGGCACUGAGGAAGGAGAGGCUGACGUGAGACAUCUCAAAGGGAACCAUGGGGAGGGAGCCUUGCUCCCUGCAAAAUAUAGAAGUUGGCUUUUUUUUUUUGUCUUCUGCUAGAAUAAAUGCUACCUUAAACUGGAAUACUAUAGACCUAUACAUAUAAACUGAAGACACAAAUCUUUUAGAAAAGAUAGGUAAAUGCAUUUAUAAUACUGGAUAGGCAUAAAUUCAUAAAGAAGACACAAAAGUCCCUAGAUAUAAAAUUUUUAAGUUCGAUAAAUAUAGGACCUCUUCACAUUAAUCAUUGUGCUCAUCAAAGUCACCAUUAAGAAAGAAGAAAUGCAAGCCACAAACCAAGUGAUCGUAUGGAAACUACAUGUACCCAGAAAUGGAACUAUUGUUCAUACAGUACAUAGAAAGAACUCCUUUAAAUCAGCAAUAAAAAAUAUAAACAACCAAAUUUUAUAAAAUUAGCAAAACAUGUGAACAUAUACUCUUACAGAAAAUACAAGGGGCUGAUAAACAUACAAAUGCUGCUUUCCACCAUUAGUAAGCAAGGAAUUGUAAAUUAAAACCACCAUGAGAUACUAUUAUAUACCCACUAAGAUGUCUGAAAUUUUUAAUGGCUUAUUUAUCAUUGAGGUUAUUGGAAAUCUAUUUCUAAUAUUGGAAAUGGUCGAUACUAGCAGAGUUUGUGCCAAUAGUAGCCAAGUCACAUUGAGUUAACAGGAGCAUAGUACACAUCCUCAAGAUCAAUAAUUAGUGACACUUCCUGUGAAGAUACACAGGUUAAUGCUUAAGGCUUUGAGGGCCAUCUUCUGCGUCAAAACAACUCAACUCUGACAAAAGCAGCCAUAGACAAUGUGUAAACAAAUGGGUGUGCCCGUGUUCCAAUAAAACUUUAUUUGUAAAAACAGGUGGCUGCUGGAAUGGUGCCCAGGGACAGUAGUUUGUGAACCCUUGUUCUAGAUCUUAAAACUAGCAUAGUUCCAGCUGAUCCCACUUUAGAGACCCUCACUGGGUGGGGCCUCAGGGAGCAUGUGAUUAGACAUGUCUUGCAGUCAAAUUCCUGUGAUCACAUUGUACUUACUUGAGAGUGAGACUUUUCCUCCUUUGACACUUUCUAAAAUAUGCCAUGACUCAAUAGCCAGUGGACUGUAAAUAUUCAUGGUUUCUC